GCUGCGCCGCAACGCAGUGGGCUCGCGGCCGCGAGCAACAGGCCGUGCCGGGUGAGUGGGGCGCUCUCGUGGGCAUCCCAGCGCCGGGGCAGGCCGGGUAGUGCCCGAUCCCGCGGGGCGCGCGCUGCUGCUUUAGGCACCCGGGCUCGGGUGCGGGUCUGGGAGACCUGUCGGUCGGCGAGAAGCCUCGGUGGCCGGCGCUGUGGUUGCGGGACCUGGGACGCGCUCCCAGGCGUCCCACCUCCCCGGAGACUGGGGCAGGGUGGGUGGGGCCCGGAUCUAGGGGUAGGGUCGCGGAAGCCUUGGUUACAGAGAGUCGCACACGUGGCCUGCUAAUGGUCGCGACACCGGUGACGAGCGCACGGAAAGUUUGGAGGCUUAGCAAGGAGGGUGGUGCCGGCCUCCGCCCGGUGGUGGCAGAACUGCCUGUGCGAGCACGGCUUCCACGUGGGCUGCGCCGCCGGGCGUCAUGUCGGGCCUAAGAGACACGCUCUACAGCUGUGAAAUCUGAAGUUCAGGUGUGUGGGGAGAAGGGCAGCUGCAUUACAUCAUAUGCUUCCAAUUCAUUUACCAGCAAAUAAUUCCGCAACGAUUGGCCGACAGCUGGGUUGUCCAACAGGUUACUGAGACCAGGUUAUUCACUGUUUUCAGGAAGGAUAGACUGGGAGGAAGAGGAUCUGAUUUCGCCACUCAUUAGCUGUAAAUCUGGUGCCUCGGGUUUCAUGUCACUGGGCUCAUCUUUGAGCAGAGGAACCUGAUUUACUCAGCUUCUUCUGCUGGUACUGGUUUUUGCCUCCUGGACAUCAAGCUUUGUAACCUCAUGGUCACGAAAAUACAUUGAGGUUUGCAUUUCCUUACUGCUUUGUCUUGAAGACAGAACGAUGCCAAAGAAAGCAAAGCCUACAGGGAGUGGGAAGGAAGAGGGGCCGGCUCCCUGUAAGCAGAUGAAGUUAGAAGCAGCUGGGGGGCCUUCAGCUUUAAACUUUGACAGUCCCAGUAGUCUCUUUGAAAGUUUAAUCUCGCCCAUCAAGACAGAGACUUUUUUCAAGGAAUUCUGGGAGCAGAAGCCCCUUCUCAUUCAGAGAGAUGACCCUGCACUGGCCACAUACUAUGGGUCCCUGUUCAAGCUAACAGAUCUGAAGAGUCUGUGCAGCCGGGGGAUGUACUAUGGAAGAGAUGUGAAUGUCUGCCGGUGUGUCAAUGGGAAGAAGAAGGUUUUAAAUAAAGAUGGCAAAGCACACUUUCUUCAGCUGAGAAAAGAUUUUGAUCAGAAAAGGGCAACGAUUCAGUUUCACCAACCUCAGAGAUUUAAGGAUGAGCUUUGGAGGAUCCAGGAGAAGCUGGAAUGUUACUUUGGCUCCUUGGUUGGCUCGAAUGUGUACAUAACUCCCGCAGGAUCUCAGGGCCUGCCGCCCCAUUAUGAUGAUGUCGAGGUUUUCAUCCUGCAGCUGGAGGGAGAGAAACACUGGCGCCUCUACCACCCCACUGUGCCCCUGGCACGAGAGUACAGCGUGGAGGCCGAGGAAAGGAUCGGCAGGCCGGUGCAUGAGUUUAUGCUGAAGCCGGGUGAUUUGUUGUACUUUCCCAGAGGAACCAUUCAUCAAGCGGACACUCCUGCGGGGCUGGCCCACUCUACUCACGUGACCAUCAGCACCUACCAGAACAAUUCAUGGGGAGAUUUCCUUUUGGAUACCAUCUCGGGGCUUGUAUUUGAUACUGCAAAGGAAGACGUGGAGUUACGGACCGGCAUACCCCGGCAGCUGCUCCUGCAGGUGGAAUCCACAACUGUUGCUACAAGACGAUUAAGUGGCUUCCUGAGGACACUUGCAGACCGGCUGGAGGGCACCAAAGAACUGCUUUCCUCAGACAUGAAGAAGGAUUUUAUUAUGCACAGACUCCCCCCUUACUCUGCGGGAGAUGGGGCAGAGCUGUCAACACCAGGUGGAAAGUUACCGAGGCUGGACAGUGUAGUGAGACUGCAGUUUAAAGACCACAUUGUCCUCACAGUACUGCCGGAUCAAGAUCAAUCUGAUGAAGCUCAAGAAAAGAUGGUGUACAUCUAUCAUUCCUUAAAGAAUAGUAGAGAGACACACAUGAUGGGAAAUGAGGAGGAAACAGAGUUUCAUGGACUUCGCUUCCCUUUGUCACAUUUGGAUGCACUGAAGCAAAUUUGGAAUAGUCCAGCUAUUUCUGUCAAGGACCUGAAACUUACUACAGAUGAGGAAAAGGAAAGCCUGGUAUUAUCCCUCUGGACAGAAUGUUUAAUUCAAGUAGUCUAGUGCCUUUGCAGAAUCAAAUGCCUACUAUUUUAUAUGCAUAUAUUAAAAGAAAAGCAAAGACCUGAGCCGAGGAGAGGAUGAAUUCAAGUUUCCUUACCUGCGUAUCUACUAACAAACAUGAGACCUCCCUGUUACAGGUGGUCAGUUGGCCAAAUGUACUAACGGGCACAUGAAAGAAAGAACAGCAAAUUACCAAGUGUCUCAGAAAAUGACAAAACCAUAUUUUGACAAGUUUAUUUAAUCCAGUGUGGUAGAAAAGGCACAAUUCCAAUGUAUCAUUUAGAAUUGAAUGUCAUUAACCUGGCUUUGUUCUUUGGAAGAAACAACUUCUUUAAAGAGCUUCUUUGGCUCUAGAAAAAUUUCAAACAAUUAAAAUAAGAAAAAAUUUUAAACUGGUUUUUUAUAAUGAAAAUAUACAUACCUUUGUGUAUAGACAAGCCCAUGCCCAUUAAAAUAAAGUUAUCCUGUAACAUAAAUUUUAUUAAAUAAUACUUCCCCACAGAUGAGAGGCACGCAACACCUAUGGACAAAAGGGAGUUACAGAGGCUGCUUAAAAGAUGGAGAAAAGCCUGAGAUUGAAGGAGGAAAAAAACCCAGUAUUUAAAGUCUAUAAAAAAUACUCAAAAUAGUGGGUCUUCGAGUUUAAAAUAGUCAUUGUUAUUUUACAUUCUAAAGUGCAUGUAGGUUGAUAUUUUUUAAAAUAUCAUUGGAGAAUUUAAUCUUUCUUUAUAAAAAUAGAGCAUUUUUCUGCUUUCUGGCAAAAGUUGGGGAUAAAAGGAAAAAAAGUUGUCAAAAUGUAAUUUUCAGUCCAAUUCACCAGGAAAACAUGCUUGUGAAUUGUGCAGUAAAAGGUGGUAAUGACUACUGGAAGCUAAGUCAAAGGUGAUUUCCUACCUGAUUUUACUUACUUAAAUAAAAGUUACUUACAAUGGGAGUGAAAAACUGAGGUUUCUGUUAUUUAGUAGAGAAAUCAACUCCACGUUUACUUAAAGAGAUGGUAAGGUCAAGGUUCAAAUGCUACUGUGUUUUAAUUUGGAUAUUUGAAAUUUCUCUUGAGGCAAAAAAAAAAAAAAAUUGAUGCCUCUCCUUAAAUCUAGGAUGAAGUGUCAACAUGGAGACAGGUAACCACUGUUAUAGAGUCUUGUCACCUAAAGGGAUGUCUUGGUUAACACGUAACAGUGCAAGUUUGGCCAUAGGUUAUUUAUUUGUACUUUUUUAGUUUGAAGGACUGAGGAAACAAUAGCUACAGAAAAUACUUCUUGUGCCUUAUUCCUAACAAAGCUGAGGUCCCUGCCUGGGGUUAGUUACAAGUAUAAAUACUUAACGAGGUGCGUUCAUUAUAAAAGCCUCAGUAUAGAAACCUUAAAGUUUAUCUAGGAAAGUUUAGUAUAUUUUCAGGUGUUGCUAAAAAAUUACUCAUCUGUUUGCAAAAGUAUGACUUGACCUAUAGAAAUCUGUUUCUUUAUGCUUUGUACUCAUACAAGCAUCUAGGUAGGAUAUUAAUAAAUAAUACAGGAUAAUAGCAUCACCAGUGUCCAAUAACGGGCCAUCAGGAACAGGAUUCACGUUUGGUGGAUAUGAGAGAAAAUAAACACUUCAGGAAACUUGCUCACCACAGCUGGAGAUCAGGAAUAGAACCUUUCCAAGAUAUCAUAAUAUUUUCUUUAUAGGAACACUGAGUAAUGGCAAGAAUAUUUUGAGCUUUUCCAUGGUUAAGAGCGAUAGUCUCAGAGGCUGGAGAAAAUGUUCAUUCUGCUCAGUGAUCCAGGAGUGUGAGGACAGUAGCUUCCUUUCCACGUCCACAAGACAAUGACAGAUGUGUUUCCUUCUUUGCUCUUUCUAGGGAUCUUUCUAGGGAUGUUGAUUCUCUCACAAUAUUUCAAUGUCCCAUUUCUGUGUUUCUUCUCCCUCCAGGGGCUGAUUUACAAUUACAUGAGUCUUGUCACAAUAAUUUCCUCCUAAAAUAGAAAUUCCAAAAGAAAAGAUUAUUUGUUCAGGCAGGUGCUUAGCAAUUUCACAAUUUUCACAAGCUUCUGUUCAGCUCACCAUUUCGGUGGAUGAAUGUGUCAUUUACAAAGAAGUCUGAAAUGGGAAGCUGAGUUUGAACAGGCUUAGCCAUUAUUCACCUCAAAUUGGACCUUAUUAUGACUCAAAUUGAAAUACUAAAAGGUAUAAUACAUGAUUGUAUAAGUGGCGUGCCUUAAUGUGAUUCUUUAGAACAAAGUGCUCUUGAGAGAACUCUGGCUGAAUGUCAGGUACUGUGUUUUUGUUUCUACACCAACAAAACUGUGACUAACCCAAUUAAAGCAACAGCCAUGAAUAAUAUUGGCCCUGACCUUGCUGAAUUCAAAAACAAGGUUAAUUGAUACCUACCAUAAAUUCUACCUGAGGGUUUUUAAGGACCAUGGCAAUUCCUGGCAAAAAGCUAGAGAUGUUUCUAAGAAACAGAUGACAUUCAUUUCAUGGUUUAUGGUGCUUGAAAUUUAGAACUGUUCUGAGUUCACGUAGCAAAUGAAAGUUUUACAACUGUACUAAUGAACAAAAACCCUAAGCUUUGUUGUUUGGCUUUUUCUGCUAAUUGUUUUGUUUGUAAAACUGCCUAUCUUAAUUUUCUUCAAGCAUAAUUUUAAAUGACUUAACAUUUCUCUUAUACAUAAGGAUGUCCUUUACCCAAAAUGAGGAGAUUUGGAACUGAAACUAAUAUCCAGGGACACAACAUUGGGUAUCAUCAAAGGCCCACCUUUAACAUCAAGGACAAGUUGAUCACUGAGAUAAGAGCUGAUAGUUCCAUUUUUAUUCAGUCUCCACUUCUGCCUGAAUUGCCCAUGUUCAGUCCAUAGAGCUACUUUAGCUCCAGGUGUGUCCCGGCCACCAAUCACAUCAAGACAUGUAUCACUGGCCUAAAAGGGUUAAGAAAUGAUUAAUUGGCAGUAGUAUGUUUGCUAAAGUAAGUUGAAUUAGGUCCCUUUUAUCUUAGGUAAACAAGUCAUAGACAUGAAGUGUGUGUGUGUCUUAUCUAAAAAAAUACUAUAUAGUAUAAUUUCAGUAAGCCUUUUUUAAUGUCUUCUUUACGGCUGUGGGUAGGAGAUGGUACAGAAAUAAACCAACUGAAAUAGAGGUACUUGUUUUUAAUAGGAUGUCUACAUCUGACAACAGAUGUUCAAUAAAGAUUUGGUGAAUUGGAAUUAAAUGUUAAAUCCCUGUUUGCUUAAAACGUAUUAUGUUGAGCUUGGUUUUCUUAUGAAAACAUUGCAUGAUGGGCUAAAGAUAUCCAGACAAUAAUUACUUUUAAAAGUUUUUCAUUUUUGAAGCAUGAGAAAAAGUAGAUAAUCCAUUGGUGAUACAAUAAAACACAGUUUGAAUGUU